AGACUAGACGCUGAGCGCUCCCGUGCGCAGCGCCCCACGCAGCCGGGACGCGGCGCCGCUCUGCGGGUGGAACCGCCGCGCGCUCCCGGCCUCGGGAGCUGAGCCCGAGAGAACUUCGCUGCCUUCGGGUCGCCGCUCCCGCUUUCCACUGUGGAAUGUGCAGCUUGGGAUAGAGAGAAACCAGGGUUUGGGGAGCGGUCCUCCUGGAGACUUUCUCUCUGCAAGUCUCCAAGGUUAAGCAAUUCUGACCCACUGGAAUUCCCAGAGCCUGGGAGUUAAGCCUAAAACGCUCUGUUGCUUUAAGCGGCGCGGUGGGGAGUCGCUGGACACUCCUUAUUUUGGUUUUACAUUAAAAAGAAGGCGGACGAGAAGAUGUUGUAGGUGACUUCCUAGCUGUGUUAAGUUGCUCCUGGGCUGUGAAUGGUGUUAAUUUCUGAAGUGGGCGGCUCCAAAAACUUAACAAGGAAAGGGGUGGCCACUCCCCUGAAUGCAGUGAUUAUCCUUCCCAAGGACGUCCUUUUUCCUGUGCUACAUAUGGGGGGACGAAGUUUCACUCUGUUGCCCAGCCUGGAGAACAGUGAUGAGAUCUCAGCUCACUGCAAGCUCUGCCUCCCGGGUUCAAGCAAUUCUCCUGCCUCAGCCUCCCAAGUAGCUGGGAUUAUAGGCACACGCCACCAUGCCUGGCUAAUUUUUGUAUUUUUAGAAGAGACUAAAUAUACAAAGGUUUAGGGUUUCGCCAUGUUGGCCAGGCUGGUCUUGAACUUCUGACCUCAAGUGAUCCUCCUUUCUCAGCCUCCCAAAGUGCUAGGAUUACAGGCAUGAGCCACAGCACCCGGCCUGAUCUUUUAAACAUAAAUGAUAAAGAAUUGAUAGGGUGAUUUCCAUUUCUUUUGCAAAAACAAAUCAUAACUUUUCCCUGUUUCUUUUCUUUUCUAUCCUUUUCUCUUUUUUUGAGAUAGUCUUGCUCUGUCGCCCAGGCUGGAAUGCAGUGGUGCAAUCUCGGCUCACUGCAACCUCCACCUCCCGGGUUCAAGCAGUUGUCUUGCCUCAGCCUCCCGAGUAGCUGGAAUUACAGGCACCUGCCACCAAGCCUGGCUAAUUUUUGUAUUUUUGGUAGAGAUGGGUUUCACCUUGUUGGUCAGGCUGGUCUCGAACUCAUGACCUCAAGUGAUCUGCUGCCUCAGCCUCCCAAAGUGCUGGGAAUACAGGCAUGAGCCACCAUGCCCAGCCCUUCCUUGUUUCUUUAAUGAUGGCUAUUCCCCCUUCCCAGGCCAGAAUUAUGGAGAUAAUUGUCUCAACUGAUUAUUUCCUCCUCCAAGAAAAGCUGAAGAAUGCAUAGUGUUAAGCACACGGGGUGCUUGAUAGCAUAGUGGUAAGGUUCAAGAGCUUUGAAGCCAAGCAGUCCAUCUGUUAGCUACGAGACCUUGGAGCUCUCUUAGCAAAGAAGAGAGGAAUGUCUAUUGCGUGGCAAUCUGUGGUGCCUGCCAAAAAAGAUAGAAUACAAAGAUUAAUCAUACAGUAAUACUCAGUCUUCAACCUCGAGGUGCUCUUAAAGGAGCCCAUGAAAUAAAAUAAUAAACCAUAGAAAAUGAUAAGUACUACUAGGUAAAAAAUCAAGGUAGAGAGUGAUAGUACUUACAAAAGAGAUACAGAAAGAAAUUGGAGUGGAAAGGAGGGAGACAGUCAGGAGGGCUUCUUGAAGGAGGUGGCCGGGAGAAACAAGGAUUUGGGUCCAUGGAAUUCAGAGCAAGAAUAUUCUGGGCUAUGAGGAUAGCAUGAGCAAAGGCAUUGAGACUGAUAUAUCAGGUUGCAUAUAGGGAACAGAGACAAGAGAGUGGCUCGGUUUGACCACGAAUGAAGUGAAAUAGAGGGAGAGAAGAGAAUAUAGGGUUGAGGUCCGGUUAGGCGAGGCCUUGAAUGUCAUGCAGAGGAGUAGCUUUGACAGUUUAUAUGCUCCUCCCCAGUAAGACGUGUAGCCGUAUAAUGAGAGCUUUCGAGACCAAGCUGUGUCGUCAAUUCUGGAAGACUGUCGUACCAGAAGGCCUUGACUUUUCCUAUCUUGGUCCAAUGUCACUCCUUGCAGAUUUGCUAUCUCAGUACAAAAGAUGUGAAAGACACUGGAACAUGCUGUUUUACAAAACAUCUCAGAAAGAGCCAGUCUGAGAAGCAGUGUGCAAUGGCCUCAGAUAUCUUGGGAAUAUUGAAUAUAUUCACAGAUGGUAGAAUCGGAGUUUGCAGUUCUGCUUUCUUUGCCCUGACCUUGUUUGAGACGUGCUUGCUUCUGAUAUGCUGAUUCCACGUUGCAAAAGUGAAACUCAGGUAACGGAGGCCUUGGAAAGAGACUCUGCGUCAGGUCACCCAGCAGAGAUCAGCAAUCCUUGGCUCACUGAGGAGGUUUGGAUUUGCCUCAAAGGGCACUGCAAAAAUUGAACAGAGGAAUCCCAAGGAAGCUGCCUGAAUUUGCCUGUAUACUCUCGUUCUGCGACUUAUAAAGGACCAGACAAAUCAAAUUAGUGGUUUUGGUUUCCGCCAGCUGUGGAUGCCUUUGACAUUAUGACCGCAGAGGAUUCCACCGCAGCCAUGAGCAGUGACUCGGCCGCCGGGUCCUCCGCCAAGGUGCCCGAGGGCGUGGCGGGCGCGCCCAACGAGGCAGCACUGCUGGCGCUGAUGGAGCGCACGGGCUACAGCAUGGUGCAAGAGAACGGGCAGCGCAAGUACGGCGGCCCACCGCCCGGCUGGGAGGGCCCGCACCCGCAGCGUGGCUGCGAGGUCUUCGUGGGCAAGAUCCCGCGCGACGUGUACGAGGACGAGCUGGUGCCCGUGUUCGAGGCCGUGGGCCGCAUCUACGAGCUGCGCCUCAUGAUGGACUUUGACGGCAAGAACCGCGGCUACGCCUUCGUCAUGUACUGCCACAAGCACGAGGCCAAGCGCGCAGUGCGUGAGCUCAACAACUACGAGAUCCGCCCGGGCCGCCUGCUCGGCGUGUGCUGCAGCGUGGACAACUGCCGCCUCUUCAUCGGCGGGAUCCCCAAGAUGAAGAAGCGCGAGGAAAUCCUGGAGGAGAUUGCCAAGGUCACCGAGGGCGUGCUGGACGUGAUCGUCUACGCCAGCGCGGCCGACAAGAUGAAGAACCGCGGCUUCGCCUUCGUGGAGUACGAGAGCCACCGCGCGGCUGCCAUGGCUCGCCGCAAGCUCAUGCCUGGCCGCAUCCAGCUGUGGGGCCACCAGAUCGCCGUGGACUGGGCCGAACCUGAGAUCGACGUGGACGAGGACGUGAUGGAGACCGUGAAGAUCCUCUACGUGCGCAACCUCAUGAUCGAGACCACCGAGGACACCAUCAAGAAGAGCUUCGGCCAGUUCAACCCCGGCUGCGUGGAGCGCGUCAAGAAGAUCCGCGACUACGCCUUCGUGCACUUCACCAGCCGCGAGGAUGCCGUGCAUGCCAUGAACAACCUCAACGGCACUGAGCUGGAGGGCUCGUGCCUGGAGGUCACGCUGGCCAAGCCCGUGGACAAGGAGCAGUACUCGCGCUACCAGAAGGCAGCCAGGGGCGGCGGCGCGGCUGAGGCAGCGCAGCAGCCCAGCUACGUGUACUCCUGCGACCCCUACACACUGGCCUACUACGGCUACCCCUACAACGCGCUCAUUGGGCCCAACAGGGACUACUUUGUGAAAGCAGGCAGCAUAAGAGGCCGAGGGCGAGGUGCAGCUGGCAACAGAGCCCCAGGGCCUAGGGGUUCCUACCUCGGGGGAUAUUCUGCUGGUCGUGGUAUAUAUAGCCGAUAUCAUGAAGGGAAAGGAAAGCAGCAAGAAAAAGGAUAUGAACUGGUGCCGAAUUUGGAAAUCCCUACCGUCAACCCAGUUGCCAUUAAACCUGGUACAGUAGCCAUCCCUGCCAUUGGGGCUCAGUAUUCCAUGUUUCCAGCAGCUCCAGCCCCUAAAAUGAUUGAAGAUGGCAAAAUCCACACAGUGGAGCACAUGAUCAGCCCCAUUGCUGUGCAGCCAGACCCAGCCAGUGCUGCUGCCGCCGCAGCCGCGGCCGCAGCCGCCGCAGCCGCUGUCAUUCCCACUGUGUCGACGCCACCACCUUUCCAGGGCCGCCCAAUAACUCCAGUAUACACGGUGGCUCCAAACGUUCAGAGAAUUCCUACUGCCGGGAUCUACGGGGCCAGUUACGUGCCAUUUGCUGCUCCAGCUACAGCCACGAUCGCCACACUACAGAAGAACGCGGCAGCCGCGGCCGCCAUGUAUGGAGGAUACGCAGGCUACAUACCUCAGGCCUUCCCUGCUGCUGCCAUUCAGGUCCCCAUCCCCGACGUCUACCAGACAUACUGAGGCUGGUGACCAGCACGAAGACAGACCACACAAACACCACUGAAGGAACGCUUGACUAUUUAUGAAGAAGGAACAUGUUGGAUUCACACAUGCAACCUGAAAGUGAAGAAUGUUAGCAGAUUUAUUUCUGAAUUAUUUUAUAUACAUGAAGUUUUCACUAGUUUUUUAAGACUAUUUUCAACUUAGCAUGCCUACGUUCAUACAUUUCCAAAAGACUUGCAAUGGUUCGUGCCUUCAUUCCAUCUUUUAAAAAUUUGUAUGCUGUACUACAUUUGUAUAGAGGUUUUUGUUGUUGUUUUUUUAAGGAUAUAUUUUCAGUAUGAAGGUUAUUUUCUUAACUUCUGCACUCCAGAGAUUUCUAUUUUGUAGUACCUUCAAUAAUAUAUCAACUAUAUAUUAAAAAAGCACACUUGAGGAGCUAGGGAACUAUUUUGAAAAAUAUAUACAAUAUUUAAAGAUACAAACAGUAGUGCUUAAAAAUACUACAUAAAGCAUUAUUUUAAAGGUUAUACUGGAAAGUGCAAUUUUAAAAUGAGUAAAACCUCUGUAUUUCUGCUGGCAUUAAGGGUUGAUGGUGUUACCAUGUAUCAUCAUGGCGGUACUAUUUUUUAAAAGAAAUUAAACACUGGAUCUCUCCUUAAGCCAACAUUGAAAAGACUUGCCGCACUUCUGAGUCCAAACACUGGAAAGCUCUCCUUUGCCACCGUUAGCCGGGGCUCAUUCUCCAUGUGCCUUAGCCUUAAACAUGCCCCCACUCCCACAUCUCUCACCCUGUCCCCUCCUCCCCAGAUUCCCAAUCCCACCGCAAUGUUUGGCAAGCCUAGGACUGAUAAGUAGCUCUGAUAGAGGAGCUGGUGGCUUUUAUACUUCUUCCUGGGUUUUUGUUGGGGUUUGUUGUUUCGUUGUUUUUUGUUUUUUUUUUUGUUUGGUUGGGGAAGUAUUGUCUUCUACGUGUGCUAUUUUCAGUAGCAGAGUAAGCACAAGGUUUUAAUCGAGUUGCAUAAGACACCUUUGCAUAGCUAUUUAAUUGCCCAAUGUAAAACUUUAAUGCCAUUUCUAAUGCUUUUAUUCAUUUUUGAAGUAUGAGUUUGUAGGGACAAAGAAUGUAUGUUAUCGUAGACAAGACCCCCAGAGACUCUUUUCAGCAGAAAGUUAUGCUUCUAGUUGCCUUACCAUGUUUCUUGCAAAACUGUCCAUGGUCCUCAAGGGUGUUGGAAACAUUAUGUUUAUUAAAUGGGCCUCUCUUCCUUUGCUGUGCACUUGAUGGGUGAACUGGAUUGGGGUGUGCACAUCCAGGAGGAGGAGGAGAGACCUGUAGAAGUUUAAAGAUAGUUUGUAAAUAUCUUCUAAUGCUUGUUUUUAGUCCUUUUAUGUUGGAGAAGUUCAUGGUAUGUAGUUUAAUGCAAAAUGAAACCAUUUUAUUUCAAUGUUAUUAAAAAGGUUUGUUUUAUUAGGAAGUUAAUGUAUUGUUGCAGUGUUUUGUGCCUGUUUAAAGGCUUUUGUUUAGCAGAGUGAAUGUAAAAUACAGUAAAAUGUUAAGAUUGUCAUCUACUUUUUAAAAAAAAAUAUCAACUUGGAAUUGUUUUUUAAAGGCUCAAUCAAGGAAGUGAGGUGUGCAAUAAGGUAGCAAGUAAAACGCAGUUGCGUUUUUAUGUCAUGUUAGAGAUCCAUACAAUUUUCCACUCACGGGAUUUUUGUUGAUGGCUGAAUUCUUGUGGAUUCAUAAGAGGAUCAUGCCCUUAGCAAGUACUUUUGUUUUGUUUUAAAUUAAGAGAUUCCCAAAUGCCUUUUUCCCCCUCAUCUUGAAAUGAGAUGAGUUUUUAUGUGUAAGCAAUAUUUAUUUAACUAUUCUAUAAAAUUAUUGAGUGCCUACUGAGGCCUUUAAGCACCGCUAACAUUCCUUUCCAUCAUUCUUUUAAAUGACAUAAAAUAAUUGUGCAAUGUUCCUGAUGAUGUACCCCACAAGCUGCAUUCAAACUCAAAUCUGUGGGAAUGAGUGACUCGACAAAAUGUAAUUCGGAUCAGAUCCUCAUCCCCUGACUGUGUGAAAAAAGUACUCUCCUUCUAGUGAAGGAUUGUCACAGAGUUUCACUGGAUGAAACUAUGACCCAGUAUUCUUACUGUAUUUUACAUAUGCCUGUAAAUUAUUUGCAAAAAAGAAGAAGAAGAGGAAGAAAGAAAAGAAAGAAAAGAAAGAAAGAAAGAAAGAAAGAAAGAAAGAAAGAAAGAAAGAAAGAAAGAAAGAAAGAAAAAGAAAGAAAGAAUAAAAAAAAAUGAUAACAUGGCAACCACCAAACUCCCUUAAAAACAAACAUUGGUGACAUGGCCAAUUAAGUAUCAGUGAGCCUCCUAUCUGGGACUUAUCUGUUCCUAUUGUUUCAAAACCAUUUCAUGUACACUACUGAGGUAAGUUUAUAACUUGAAAUGUGAACUUUUUUUUUUUUUAGUGUUAAGAACAAACUAUAUAAAUGUAAAAAAAAAGUUUUAGAGUUCUGUUUUCAAACAUUGCUAGUGGUUUAGUUAACUUUAGCUGCUUUAUAUUUGAAAAGCUUUUAUUUAGAUCUUGCUCCAUUUACAGUACAUUCUUAGGAUGUAUGUAGUAAAUAAAGCUUUCUUUAAAGCAA